GGCGUCGGCCUAGGUGCGCUGCGAGCGCGCGCGGACCGCGCACAGGCGGCGGAGCCGGUAUGGGCCCGCCUGACCCUGGGCGCCGCGCCGCACGAGCACCAGCCUAGAGCCAGGUAGGCGGCACUGGGCCGGGGCUGGGGGCGGAGACGGAAGCGGGGGUCUCCGGGCGGCCGUGCGAGCCAGGGCAGGUGCUGGGGCCGUCGAGCUGGCGUGGUCCCCCUCACCUGGCGGCUCUCCGCCGUUCGGGGCCGGGAGUGUCGCCGAGGGUCGGGGAGACGUCCUGGUCCUACGUUCCUACUUCCCGCUCUCCCGGCUGCGCCCCGGGCCUGCAUUUUGGGGCGGGAACCCAGAGACUGCUCUUUCUCUCCGGGCCCCGGGUCUGGCCCGUCCGGCCGGGCGGGGAGGGCCGGGCAUCCCAGCCCGCAGUCCUGAGGAGGCGACGGGCCCUUCUUGGUCACCGGAUCUGUUUACACGUCACCCUCGAUGCCCGGCCGUCCCUCCACGCCCAGUAACUUGGGCUCUCAGGUGCCUGCCCGGGGCCUUGGUGCUGGAGUGGGGGCUGUGGGGGCAGCACAGGUACUCUGAUUUUGGGGCCACGAGGGCCAAAUCCGCGCCUGCACGUAGGAGGUGCGCAGUGGACACGUGCGAGGUGGACGAGGGAAGGACCCUGGCUCCUACUGCAUUCGAGCGAUAGGUCUGGCACCCUAGCUUCCUUCGGAACCACUCCUGAGUGACCUUGGGCAGGCCACCUCGUCUCCCCGAGCCUUAGUUUUCCCCGGCGGAGGGGGGCGGACAGUCCCUGCUUUAGAGGUCAUUGCCAGGGUUGUUGAGGCAACAGAUGUUUCGAGGGCGGUGGAUGAGGGUUGGGUUAAAGUCUCACAGUGGGCCGGGUGCGGUGGCUCACGCCUGUAAUCCCAGUGCUUUGGGAGGCUGAGGCGGGCGGAUCACGAGGUCAGGAGAUCGAGAUCAUCUUGGCCAACAUGGUGAAACCCUGUCUCUACUAAAAAUGCAAAAAUUAACUAGGCGUGGUGGUGCGCGCCUGUAGUCCCAGCUACUUGGGAGGCUGAAGCAAGAGAACCGCUUGAACGGGGGUGGAUGUUGCAGUGAGCCAAGAUGGUGCCACUGCACUCCAGCCUGGCAACAGUGCGCAGAGCGAGACGCCGUCUCAAAACAAAAGUCUCACAGUGGCCCAGCCUCCUUUCCUGCCAUCCCUGGAGUUGUGGUCUGUUUGAGGUUUGGUUUUCAGGACUGAAGCUUCAAGAUGGCUGACCAGGACCCUGCGGGCAUCAGCCCCCUCCAGCAAAUGGUGGCCUCAGGCACCGGGGCUGUGGUUACCUCUCUCUUCAUGACACCCCUGGACGUGGUGAAGGUUCGCCUGCAGUCUCAGCGGCCCUCCAUGGCCAGCGAGCUGAUGCCUUCCUCCAGACUGUGGAGCCUCUCCUAUACCAAAUUGCCCUCCUCUCUCCAAUCCACAGGGAAGUGCCUCCUGUAUUGCAAUGGUGUCCUGGAGCCUCUGUACCUGUGCCCAAAUGGUGCCCGCUGUGCCACCUGGUUUCAAGACCCUACCCGCUUCACUGGCACCAUGGAUGCCUUCGUGAAGAUCGUGAGGCACGAGGGCACCAGGACCCUCUGGAGCGGCCUCCCCGCCACCCUGGUGAUGACUGUGCCAGCUACCGCCAUCUACUUCACUGCCUAUGACCAACUGAAGGCCUUCCUGUGUGGUCGAGCCCUGACCUCUGACCUCUACGCACCCAUGGUGGCUGGCGCGCUGGCCCGCCUGGGCACCGUGACUGUGAUCAGCCCCCUGGAGCUUAUGCGGACAAAGCUGCAGGCUCAGCAUGUGUCGUACCGGGAGCUGGGUGCCUGUGUUCGAACUGCAGUGGCUCAGGGUGGCUGGCGCUCACUGUGGCUGGGCUGGGGCCCCACUGCCCUUCGAGAUGUGCCCUUCUCAGUGCAUCCCCCACCCCAAGCCCUGUACUGGUUCAACUAUGAGCUGGUGAAGAGCUGGCUCAAUGGGUUCAGGCCGAAGGACCAGACUUCUGUGGGCAUGAGCUUUGUGGCUGGUGGCAUCUCAGGGACGGUGGCUGCAGUGCUGACUCUACCCUUUGACGUGGUAAAGACCCAACGCCAGGUCGCUCUGGGAGCGAUGGAGGCUGUGAGAGUGAACCCCCUGCAUGUGGACUCCACCUGGCUGCUGCUGCGGAGGAUCCGGGCCGAGUCGGGCACCAAGGGACUCUUUGCAGGCUUCCUUCCUCGGAUCAUCAAGGCUGCCCCCUCCUGUGCCAUCAUGAUCAGCACCUAUGAGUUCGGCAAAAGCUUCUUCCAGAGGCUGAACCAGGACCGGCUUCUGGGCGGCUGAAAGGGGCAAGGAGGCAAGGACCCCGUCUCUCCCACGGAUGGGGAGAGGGCAGGAGGAGACCCAGCCAAGUGCCUUUUCCUCAGCACUGAGGGAGGGGGCUUGUUUCCCUUCCCUCCCGGCGACAAGCUCCAGGGCAGGGCUGUCCCUCUGGGCGGCCCAGCACUUCCUCAGACACAACUUCUUCCUGCUGCUCCAGUCGUGGGGAUCAUCACUUACCCACCCCCCAAGUUCAAGACCAAAUCUUCCAGCUGCCCCCUUCGUGUUUCCCUGUGUUUGCUGUAGCUGGGCAUGUCUCCAGGAACCAAGAAGCCCUCAGCCUGGUGUAGUCUCCCUGACCCUUGUUAAUUCCUUAAGUCUAAAGAUGAUGAACUUC